GUUCUUACUUCGAAGGCUGUGCUCCGCUCACCAUCCAGAGCGGAGGUGCGGACCUUAAACUCACUCCUGGAGAAAGAUCUGCAAGUGCGCAGAGAGAAGACUGGCAGUGGAGCAUGCAUCUGGAGGGCAGAGACGGCAGGCGGUACCCCGGCGCGCCGGCGGUGGAGCUCCUGCAGACGUCCGUGCCCAGCGGACUCGCUGAACUUGUGGCCGGCAAGCGCAGGCUUCCUCGGGGAGCCGGUGGAGCUGACCCCUCGCACUCCUGCCCCAGGGGGGCUGCCGGGCAGAGCUCUUGGGCUCCUGCAGGCCAGGAGUUUGCUUCAUUCCUCACAAAAGGGAGGUCUCACUCUUCUUUGCCCCAGAUGUCCAGCUCCAGGUCUAAAGAUUCCUGCUUUACAGAAAACACUCCUUUGCUGAGGAAUUCCUUACAGGAGAAAGGGUCACGGUGCAUACCUGUUUACCAUCCAGAGUUCAUCACUGCUGAAGAGUCUUGGGAAGACAGCUCUGCUGACUGGGAGCGAAGAUACCUGCUAAGCAGGGAGGUGUCUGGUCUGUCUGCAUCUGCCUCCUCCGAGAAGGGAGACCUUCUGGACAGCCCGCACAUCCGACUCCGUCUUUCCAAGCUGAGGCGCUGUGUGCAGUGGCUGAAAGUCAUGGGCCUGUUUGCCUUUGUGGUGCUGUGUUCUAUUUUGUUCAGCCUAUAUCCGGAUCAAGGAAAGCUCUGGCAGCUGUUGGCCUUAUCACCGCUGGAGAACUACUCCGUGAACCUUAGCAGCCACGUGGACUCCACGCUGCUGCAGGUGGACCUGGCAGGGGCCCUAGUGGCCAGUGGGCCGAGUCGUCCUGGGAGGGAAGAGCACAUCGUGGUGGAGCUGACCCAGGCUGACGCUUUGGGCUCCAGGUGGCGGCGGCCACAGCAGGUCACUCACAACUGGACGGUGUAUUUAAAUCCGAGGAGAAGCGAGCACUCAGUGAUGAGCAGGACCUUUGAGGUACUGACCAGAGAGACGGUGUCCAUCAGCAUCCGGGCCUCCCUGCAGCAGACCCAGGCUGUCCCUCUUUUGAUGGCUCAUCAGUACCUCCGCGGAAGUGUAGAAACCCAGGUGACCAUCGCGACGGCCAUCCUCGCGGGCGUCUACGCGCUGAUCAUAUUUGAGAUCGUGCACAGAACUCUGGCAGCCAUGCUGGGUUCCCUUGCAGCACUGGCAGCACUGGCUGUGAUUGGCGAUAGACCCAGCCUGACCCAUGUGGUGGAGUGGAUUGAUUUUGAGACGCUGGCCCUGCUGUUUGGCAUGAUGAUCUUAGUAGCCAUAUUUUCAGAAACGGGAUUUUUCGAUUAUUGUGCUGUAAAGGCAUACCGGCUCUCCCGGGGACGGGUGUGGGCCAUGAUCAUCAUGCUCUGUCUCAUCGCGGCCGUCCUCUCUGCCUUCUUGGACAACGUCACCACCAUGCUCCUCUUCACGCCUGUGACCAUAAGGUUGUGUGAGGUGCUCAACCUUGAUCCAAGACAAGUCCUGAUUGCAGAAGUGAUCUUCACAAACAUUGGAGGAGCUGCCACUGCCAUCGGGGACCCUCCAAAUGUCAUUAUUGUUUCCAACCAAGAGCUGAGGAAGAUGGGCCUGGACUUUGCCGGAUUCACUGCACACAUGUUCAUUGGGAUUUGUCUUGUUCUCCUGGUCUGCUUUCCGCUCCUCAGACUCCUUUACUGGAACAGAAAGCUUUAUAACAAGGAACCCAGUGAGAUUGUUGAACUGAAGCACGAGAUUCACGUCUGGCGCCUGACUGCUCAGCGCAUCAGCCCGGCCAGCCGCGAGGAGACAGCUGUGCGCCGCCUGCUGCUGGGGAAGGUGCUGGCACUGGAGCACCUGCUCGCCCGGAGGCUGCACACCUUCCACAGACAGAUCUCACAGGAGGACAAAAAUUGGGAGACCAAUAUCCAAGAACUCCAAAAAAAGCAUAGGAUAUCUGACGGGAUUCUGCUCGCCAAAUGCCUGACAGUGUUGGGAUUUGUUAUCUUCAUGUUUUUCCUCAAUUCGUUUGUCCCUGGCAUUCAUCUUGAUCUUGGAUGGAUUGCUAUUCUGGGUGCCAUCUGGUUGCUAAUUUUAGCUGAUAUUCAUGAUUUUGAGAUAAUUCUACACAGAGUGGAAUGGGCAACCCUUCUGUUUUUUGCAGCGCUCUUUGUUCUGAUGGAGGCAUUGGCACAUCUCCACUUAAUAGAAUAUGUUGGAGAACAAACUGCUUUGCUAAUAAAGAUGGUCCCAGAGGAGCAGCGCCUCAUAGCCGCCAUUGUCCUGGUGGUGUGGGUCUCAGCCCUGGCGUCGUCCCUGAUUGACAACAUCCCGUUCACUGCUACCAUG